AUCCCUCGGCGCCCCGCCCGGAACCGGCGCGCGCGUAGGGGCUGGGAGGCCGGCGCGCAGAUCUGGCGGUGAGCGCUGCCGCCCCGGGGCCCCCAGCCAUGUCGGCCGAGGAGAUGGUGCAGAUCCGCCUGGAGGACCGCUGCUACCCGGUGAGCAAGAGGAAGCUCAUCGAGCAGAGCGACUACUUCCGCGCCCUCUACCGCUCCGGCAUGCGCGAGGCCCUGAGCCAGGAGGCCGGCGGCCCGGAGGUGCAGCAGCUGCGCGGCCUCAGCGCGCCGGGCCUGCGGCUGGUGCUGGACUUCAUCAACGCCGGCGGGGCCCGCGAAGGCUGGCUCCUGGGCCCGCGCGGGGAAAAGGGCGGCGGGGUGGACGAGGACGAGGAGAUGGAUGAGGUGAGCCUGCUGUCCGAGCUGGUGGAGGCGGCCUCCUUCCUGCAGGUCACGUCCCUGCUGCAGCUGCUGCUGUCCCAGGUGCGGCUCAAUAACUGCCUGGAGAUGUACCGCCUGGCGCAGGUGUACGGGCUGCCCGACCUGCAGGAGGCCUGCCUGCGCUUCAUGGUCGUCCACUUCCACGAGGUGCUGUGCAAGCCCCAGUUCCACCUCCUGGGGUCUCCUCCCCAAGCUCCAGGGGAUGUCAGCCUGAAGCAGAGGCUGAGGGAGGCCCGGAUGACUGGGACUCCUGUCCUCGUGGCCCUCGGGGACUUCCUGGGGGGACCCCUGGCCCCUCACCCCUACCAGGGGGAGCCCCCGUCCAUGCUCAGGUACGAGGAGAUGACUGAGCGUUGGUUCCCGCUGGCCAACAACCUUCCUCCCGACCUGGUCAAUGUCAGGGGCUAUGGGUCUGCCAUCCUGGACAACUACCUCUUCAUAGUGGGCGGGUACAGGAUCACUAGCCAGGAGAUCUCCGCUGCGCAUUCCUACAACCCCAGCACCAACGAGUGGCUCCAGGUGGCCUCCAUGAACCAGAAGAGGUCUAACUUCAAACUUGUGGCUGUUAAUUCAAAACUCUAUGCCAUCGGAGGGCAGGCCGUUUCUAACGUUGAGUGUUACAACCCCGAGCAGGAUGCGUGGAAUUUUGUGGCGCCCUUACCCAAUCCUCUGGCUGAGUUCUCUGCCUGUGAGUGUAAGGGAAAAAUUUAUGUCAUUGGAGGAUACACUACCAGAGACAGCCUCUGGAGAUCCUGUGUUGCUACUUGUCAUGUUUCUUAGGAUCAGCUAUCAAGAAUAAUCUACUUGCUGCCCAGCCUGGCUUCUGUAUUAAGUAGUCGGUAAUUUUGUAGCUAUUGAUGAGGGUUCUGAGGCACUUACUUUUUUUACACUGACCUGGUGGUUCAAAGGUGUGGGGAUACCAGGGAGGAGGGGCUGUGUGAAAGUCAGAGCUGCGCUUUUUCCUGGUUUUAUCCAGUCUGAGUCUCCCACGGAAGAGACGUUUGGGAGUGGGAGGUGAGUGCGGAUGGAUCUAAAUAUAUCUCUUCCCAGCCACUUUGAAAACUGUUUUUCUAACUUGUGCUUUUUCUGAAAGAGUUUUUUCUCUUUGUUACCAAAUUAUGCAGGCAGAGGUAGACAUUUCUGUACAGACUUGCCUAGUGGUGUUAGUGGAGGCGGUGUCAUCACUUGUCUUUCUUUCUUUCAGACCGGAACAUGAACAUUUUGCAGUACUGCCCCUCUUCCGACAUGUGGACGCUCUUUGAAACAUGUGACGUCCACAUUCGCAAGCAGCAGAUGGUGUCUGUGGAAGAGACCAUCUACAUCGUGGGGGGGUGUCUCCACGAGCUGGGGCCCAACCGCAGGAGCAGCCAGAGCGAGGACAUGCUCACCGUGCAGUCCUACAACACCGUCACCCGCCAGUGGCUCUACCUCAAGGAGAACACGUCCAAAUCGGGUCUUAACUUGACUUGUGCGCUCCAUAACGACGGCAUCUACAUCAUGAGCAGAGACGUCACCCUGUCGACCAGCUUGGAACACCGAGUGUUCCUCAAGUACAACAUCUUUUCAGAUAGUUGGGAAGCAUUUCGGCGUUUUCCAGCUUUUGGACAUAACUUGCUGGUUUCUUCUCUUUAUCUGCCCAAUAAAGCAGAAACAUGACUGAAUUGAAUUGGUAGAUGAAAAAAACCUGGUUCAAGUUUUUUUUAAAAUGUGGUGUCCCAUUCCAAGGGAGACCAAUUCCUAAAGGGUAAAGAAGGGUUAAAGUAGGUCACAUAUAUACAGUAGCAGCUGUAAAUAAGCUUACUUGAACUAAUUACUUGAAAACUGGUGGAAAAAAGAGACCAACUUUGUUAUUUUUUAAAUUAUUGAUUUUUAAAUUAUGGGAGCAAAUCCAUCUCCAAACAUGAUACUCUUGGGCCAAUGACGGAUCAUCAAAAUGUAGAUUCAUUGUGUCUGUGUGGUAAAGGGCCAAAGUCAAUAAUUGGGACAAAUGGUAAAGAUGAUUUUAAAAUCUGUUGUAUUUAGGUCCCUUGACAUAUCAUUAGCACCUUAAGUGAGAGGUUUUCUUUUUCUUAUCAGUGUCCUUGACAAGCAUUCAUAUUAACAUAUUCAUUCUCUCUUCUCCAUCACCCAUACCCACACAUACAUCUAGUAUGUUUAGGGUUCUGUGUUCAGAUAUUUUGUUUGCACACUACUUUUUAGGAAACUUAUAAUGAUGGAGCCCUACAGUGAAUCCUUACCAGUGUUCAGUCCUCCCCAAAACUUGCAUAAAAAUAUUCUUAGCUAUUUUUCCAGCCUUUUUUGCAGUUACAAAUGCUGGAUAAAUAGACUGAUAAAACCUCUUAUUUUAUUUAUGUGGCAGGUUGCAUAUUUAUGUGGACACAUAGGUUGCACUGCUAGGCAUUCUGUAUUGUUUUAAAGAGGAUAUAUUAUUUAGAAAAAUGGACAUAUGAAUAUUAUUAAAAAUUGAGUCUUAAAUUUAAAUGGGAAGGGAAGAAAACACCAAAUAAGAAAAAAAUUUGCCUUUAAGAGUUACUUUUGUUGAAUGUAUUUGACUUAGUUCUUAUUUUAAGGCUAAAAAAACUUUGUCAUAUUUAAGUCGGCAGCUUUCUAAUUUAAUCUUAGCUUUGUAAUUCAUGUUUUGCUUUUGUGGACUAAGGUAAGGACAGCAUUUAAAUAUUUGUGCUGGAGUGAGGGGAAGAAGCUGUUACAGAAGUGGAAUGGUUUCUGGUGGUAUUUCUGAAGUUAGGUAAAGUGCUUUACUUGCCUUGGUUGUUAAUUGAAAUAGAAUUCAGCUCAAGCAGUUGUUUUCAGUGAGUGAGUUAACAAUAAAAGCUUCUGCCAAUCAUAGAUCAACAUUCCUCAAAAAUACAUACACUCAUACUUAUGGAAAUUUUAUUUUGAUUGAAAACACUCUGAAAUUAUCUGAUAUUUUGUAAUGGCAUCAGUUAAACUGUGAGCUGGAUUCCAUCUUUCUGCAGUAACAGCGGGCAGAACCAUUUCAGUUAGCAUGUGCCUCACUUUAAGAAAGUCCUGUAGGGGAAAAAAAAAACUGUCAGAGCGAAUUCAUGCAUUCAACAAACACUUAUGAGUGCCUGGAGUAUGCCGUCCACUGUGCAGAUGUAGGACAGGGGCUAAUCACUUAGAGUUCUUCAGUUUAUUAGAGGAGUGACUACAGGUUUUCUUUACAACCAUGGCCUCUAGUAUACUUAAAAUAAGCGUCCAGUUAUAAAAAGCCUAUUUGCACAACUUUUUGGGAAUACUUCUAUUAACUAAAAUGAGGUAAGCCAUUAUUUUGGACAUAGAAACAGAUCUUUGUAUCUUGUCACCAAAUAAUCUUACCUCUAGUCUACUUACAACUUUGUAAGGGUUUCUAAGCUAUGCCCAUUUAUUCCCAAAUAUUAAGCCCUUAAAAAAAUAAAACCUCUGAACCAAAAUCUUCCCAGGAAUAGUACUUAAUAGAUUUUAAUGUUAAUUUAUAUUCAUUGUAGAAUUGAAUUUCCAGUGACCUGUAAUUUCAUUACAUAUAUUUUAAAAUCUAUUUAUUUUAGAUGGUGUUAACUUUUCGUUGCUGAAGAGCUUAACUUUUUAAAGGCUUUGUCCUAUACAUUUAGAAGAUGAGUCAGUUGAAUUAGUACUGGACAAACAGUUGGAGAUUAGUUUGCAAAUAAGCAUAUCAUAUCAAAUACAAUAUUCCAGCCAACCAGUUAAUUCUCUUCCUGGUUACAUUCAUUGGGUCUAUUUGCCUAAUGUUGACAAUUAGAUUCUUGGACCAAGUGAGGGUGUACUCUGAUCCACAAAGCUCUUUUAUAAACCAGGUUUGAGGUUGUGUGUGUGUGUGGGGGUGUGUGUGUGUGUGUGUGUGUAUGUUUGCAUAUUAUAGCUCUCUUUAAGACAGACAUCUAAAAAGAUUUUGGUUAUUCUGGGCUGCCAGCAGUACGUGGGAAAGGUGGAAUGUGCAAUAGGAACAGAUCUGUGCAUUUUGUGACAUCGUCCUUCCUGCUGUGCACAUCAGCUGUGAUGACAUUUUGAGGGUAGUUUUAAUUUAGCUCGGUUCUCUUGUUGGUGCCAGUAUUACAUUGAAGACUACCUAUGAUAGAGGCAAUGUUGCUUUGAAAAUCUCCCUUCAGGCGGAGGUUGCAGUGAGCCGAGAUUGUGCCAUUGCACUCCAGCCUGGGCGACAGUGCAAGACUCUGUCUCCAAAAAAAAAAAAAGAAAAAAGAAAAUCCCCCUUCAUCCCCCAGGACUGUCCUUUACUCUUUGAUAGUAUCCCUCUAUUUUCUUCCCAAUUCUCUAAAUGCUUUAUCAUUUUUUCCUGAGAUGCUUCUGAGGGAUGCUGACCUCCCACUAUGGGGAAAAGGGUUGCUUGGAGGACCUGGGGUGGCAGCCCCCCGACCAGAAGCACCCUAUUUUAUAGAUAGCAGUCUGAAUGGUAGAGAGUCCUGUGUGUGGGUUGUUAGAAGGUUGGUUCUUCCUGUUAUUCUCUCUGGCUUUCCUUUCAACCCACUUAUUUUCAGAGGCCUCUCCCCUUAGCAUCCUUUAAAAGGUUUUCUGAUGAAUGUGUGAAAGAGUUGAUUAUUUCAACAGUAUUGGUUAAGUCACAACGACGAAGUGCUGAGAAGGUUAUGGGUACCAGGAAGAAACAAACAGAAGUCUUAAGAUUAGAAUGAGAACCAAAGAGAAUUUAACCCUGCCAUUUUUUUUUUUUUAACACCAAGAUCCUAAGUAAUUCCAAAUGCCUUAGAUAUCAAUGAAAGCUACACACCAUUGAGAUGGGCAAAAUUCUUUCUCUACAAAGGGAGUAAUCAAGUAAAUACCUGUUCUCUUUCAAUGGACUGUUGCCUAUUGAGCAUUGUGGAUGAUGUGUUUUCAGAUUUCCAGGUGAAGUUCUGACCCUACCUGUUUGGCCAAAGACGUAAAUUGAGAGGAAAGGCCUUGGUCUUCCUGAUCAACCAGCAUUUAACGAACAGUGGCUUAAUGCAGAUCACUCAAGAGGCAGCAUAGCAAUGUAAAAGGAAUAUAAGUAGGUGUUGGAUGCCUUUUUCCUAGACCAGGAAUGGGGAAUAUAUAACACCUGUGCCACCGCUCUUUUAAGGAGGCAUUAUGAAUGAGUGCAGCAUUCCUGUCCUCUGUGCCAGGAUUUGGUCUUAGAAUCCAUGUCAGAUUGGUGCUUCCAGACAUCUAUUCCCAGUCCAUCAGAGUGAAAUGAAGGCUAUUUGCCAUCCCUGCCUUAGACAGAGGAGUGAAAGAAUUAAGUGGGUAGACACCAACCAAAAUGACUUUGAAAGCAGUGAGCUGAUUGAGCUCCAGUUCUGUGGUUACCAGAAAUACUGAGUGUCUGUCAUGUGCAAGACAAUGCUAAGAACAGAAUACAGACAUAAAUAAGUCACGGCCCAUGACCUUGAAGAGCUUACGGCCUUAUAAAGAGGUUCACUGUAAUUGUCUUCACCAGGGCGUCCUUCUCAAAGAUGCCCACUUUUGUCUGGCACAUUGGGGCUCGGUGGUCUGGUGGUCCCUUCGGUCUUGGCCCUGUCCGUCCUUUGUUUUUGUGAUUUACUAACAAUCAUCACGAACCAGUUUUGUUUUUCUUUUAAAUUUGAACAUCACAUCUUGUGUUUUAGUUUUUUGCUCUAUGAUUUUUUUCUCACUGCUUUUCAGUCUUCUCUGUACUUCAUUUUUGUGAAAAAGUGAAAAUCACAUAUAAUCUUUAUUUAAAAAUGCUCACCAAGCACUGCAGACUUUGGAGUUAGGGAUUCAGCAGCUUGUUCCAGUGAAAAGGAGGAGUGAAGCUGGGGAAGUUAGUAUCUAAGAGGGGCAAGCUGAUUGCAUGUGCAUUUAUACCUAUGCCUUUAAAACAUUCCCAUAAAAAGUAUUAAUAAAGAAAUUUCCAUUCCACACUAGUACUGAUGAAAAGGUGGUUGAUUUUGCCUUGUGAUAAUUAUCAAAGGAUAGUUUUUCAUCCUUAGAUUUUAUUCACAUGAGAGAUUUUUUUUAUUUUCUCUGUUGACUUAGGAACACAUCAUAAAUUCACACCAACUGACACGUUGCUGACGUCUGUACUUGACAUAACCAUUUUUAUUCAUACAGGAAGCAUUAAAUAUAAAAGAUGGUCAGUUUUGAAGAGCAAAGGGUGCUGAAAUGACUUGUACGGUUGGCUGGUGCUUUCUCAAAUGGAUUGCCAUAGUUCAUUACUAGUAAAGAAAAGGAAAAUGUGAUUUACGUUGUCAUUUUUCCUAUUAAAAAAAACCCUUAAGAAUGGGGCACUUGAGCUGUCCCUGCAAUGUUUUCAUAUCUAGUAGUCAUUUUAGGGAAAGUGAUAAUCUGUAGAAUGAAUAGUUAUGUUUUGAUAUGACUGAUACUUUCUUUGUUAAAAGGUUGUAUUAAGUCUUCAAUUUCAAGUCUAGCUUAAAAGUGUAAACAUUAUGUGAUUCAUUUGAAUACAAGAAUGCCUAUGAAAUACCCACUAUAACAGCAUUCCUUUUGUGUUUAGAACUAUAGAAGAAAAUGUCUUCAAAUAAAGUAGUUUUCAGUCA